UCUAUGGCCAGUCUGGCCGCCAUGUUGGAGCUUUCGCUGUUCGGGGCCCGGCCUGCUCCGGGCCCUCCCAGCGUCGCCGCUAGCUGACUUAGGGCUCCCGCCCACACUGCGCACGGCCUUGCUGAGGGCCGGCUCGUAGUGGGAGGCUUCGCGUUCACCUGAACAUUUCCGCCUCCUCUGGAUGGGGGAUGAGAGGCGGGGCUGAUGCAUCGCAGCAGUCCUGGACCCUGACUUCGGACUUGGAGAAGAAACGCCGAGGAGGAACGGGAGUUAGGGGGUUAGCAGCUUGGCGCGCUGGGAGCCGGCCACCCCUGGUCUCCGGACUUCACUUCCCAGGAGGCCUCGCGCGCGACUGGAAGUGCUGCGAGCCUAUAAGAAGGCGAGGCGGCACCCGCCGCUCUGCUCUGGGGCGGCAUUGCCAGCCGGCUGUAGGCAUUCAGGGCAGUGUCUUCUGCAUCUCCUAGGAACCUCGGGAGCGGCAGCUCCGGCGCCUGGUAGCGAGAGGCGGGUUCCGGAGAUCCCGGCCUCACUUCGUCCCACUGUGGUUAGGGGAAUAUUGAGCCCUUCACUCCUCAUGUUCCGACUUUAACAGAAGCUACCUUUGAGAAUAAGGAAUCCUCAGAGCUGAGAGGGAGUGGACCCGAAUUCCUGUACCAGCUCGGCCACUUACCUUGGCUAAGUCAUUUUCUUGUUUUGGGCCCCAGUGUCACAGUGUUUUUGAUUUGUAAGAUGAGGGUUUAGGGCUUGUAUCCUAAAUCUGGUCCUCAAGAUUCUUGAAGUCCCCCAGUCCAUCGGGGAGGGAGAGCAACAAACUGAUUUUCUACCCCUUCAUUUAUUUGUAGUUCUAAAUUAUAAAAGUAACACUGCAAGAGUUUGGAGUAGAGCCUUUUUCUUUUUCUUUCUUUUUUUUUUUUCUGAGACAGAGUCUCACUCUGUCGCCCAGGCUGGAAUGCAGUGGCACGAUCUCGGCUCACUGCAACCUCCGCCUCCCGGGUUCAAGCGAUUCCCCUGCCUCAGCCUCCCAAGUAGCUGGGAUUACAGGCGCCCGCUACCGCGCCCGGCUAAUUUUUGUAUUUUUAGUAGAGACGGGGUUUCUCCAUGUUGGUCAGGCUGGUCUCGAACUCCUGACCUCAUGUGAUCCGCCCGCCUCGGCUUCCCAAAGUGCUGGGAUUACAGGCGUGAGCUACCGCGCCCAGCCUGCGUAGAGCCUUUUUCUAAGACUAAGGGCUGGAUGGGAACUAGCAUUUCUUACCCCUGGAUGUGACCUGUUUUAGCUCAGCCGGGAGAAUCCUUUUUCGCAAGAAGUUAAUAAUAUCUUGUGACGUGAAAAUUAUGUGAAACUCAGACUUCAGUGUCCAUAAAUAAAUAUUACUGGAACACAGCCGUGGUGCUCAUUUGUUAAGAUGUUUAUGUGGCUGCUCUUGCAUGGGCAGAGUUGAUGACAUAGUUGUGACAGACCAUGUGCUCUACAAAGCCUAGAAUAUUUACUACCUGGACCUUUACAGAAGAGCUUGCUGACUGCUCCCUUAGAAUGGGGCUCUGCAAAGUGAGCACACCCUGGGAUCACAGCCCAGCCUGCCCUUAGAACAAAUGAGAGGAUAUUUUCAAGCAUUUGCAUUGCAGUUUUCACGGUUUUUUUGUUUUGUUUUGUUUUUGAGACAGAGUCUAGCUCUGUCGCCCAGGCUAGAGUGCAGUGGUGCGAUCUCGGCUCACUUCAGCCUUCUCCUGGGCUCAAGCCAUCCUCCCACCUCAGCCUCCUGAGUAGCUGAGACUACAGGUGGAUGCCAUCACGCCCAGCUAAUUUUUUUUUUUUUUUAAGAGAUGAGGGCUCACUGUUGCUCAGGCUGGUCUGGAACUCCUGGGUAUUUAUUUAUAGACAGAGUCUAUCUCUGUUGCACAGGCUGCAGUGCAGUGGCGUGAUCUUGGCUCACUGCAACCUCUGCCUCCUGGGUUCAAGCAAUUCUCGUGCCUCAGCUUCCCGAGUACCUUGGACUACAAGCGCAUGCCACCGUGCCUGGCUAAUUUUUGUAUUUUUAGUAGAGACGGGAUUUUGCCAUGUUGGCCAGGCUGGUCUCGAACCCCUGACUUCAGGUAACCCACCUGCCUGGGCCUCCCAAAGUGCUGGGAUUACAGGCAUGAAUCACUGUGCUGGUCCUUCACUGCAUUCUUCCUUUUCUCCUGCUUUGCUCUAUUUCAGGAAGUAGGAGGGCUUAUCUGUGUAUUGUGAGCAGGGCAAUAUAACUUUGCAGCUCUCUGUCAGGAAAGUGUGCCCAGGGUCUAUUCUAAGUCUGUCACAGAGCAGUAAACCAGGACCUUUUCUAGGGUGUGGCUACAGAUCCUUUCGGACUGCAUUUACUUUUUCCUCUUACAAAGAAAAAAAAAACAGUUGUGGAAGUAGAUAUUGUCAGAUGAGUGAGCCUGCUGAUCAAGAUCUCUUACAUUUCACUGAGGGAUGGAGAGUGUUUUAGGUGAGUCCUGCAAAUGUUAAGUGAUUUGCUCAAGGUGCCCAUUUCGCAGGAAUUGGAGCCCAGGCCAGUUCUCUGAGCCUAUCAUUAGGGCUAAAGAGGAAGAGAAAGCAGAAGUCUCAGGGCUGGAGACAGCUGAGGGGCAUCAGCUGGUUCAAGGUGUGGAGUGUGGGCAGUGGAGUGAAGGCCUGGUUACCUCUCCAGUGAAGAUUAGCCCCAUAGAGCUUACUCUAUGGGGAAGAACUUUUCUGACUCCUUCCUGUCUAGGGAGUGCGUGAUCAGAAUGGUGUCUGGACGGUUCUACUUGUCCUGCCUGCUGCUGGGGUCCCUGGGCUCUAUGUGCAUCCUCUUCACUAUCUACUGGAUGCAGUACUGGCGUGGUGGCUUUGCCUGGAAUGGCAGCAUCUACAUGUUCAACUGGCACCCAGUGCUUAUGGUUGCUGGCAUGGUGGUAUUCUAUGGAGGUGCGUCACUGGUGUACCGCCUGCCCCAGUCGUGGGUGGGGCCCAAACUGCCCUGGAAACUCCUCCAUGCAGCGCUGCACCUGAUGGCCUUCGUCCUCACUGUUGUGGGGCUGGUUGCUGUCUUUACGUUUCACAACCAUGGAAGGACUGCCAACCUCUACUCCCUUCACAGCUGGCUGGGCAUCACCACUGUCUUCCUCUUCGCCUGCCAGUGGUUCCUGGGCUUUGCUGUCUUCCUCCUGCCCUGGGCGUCCAUGUGGCUGCGCAGCCUCCUAAAACCUAUCCACGUCUUUUUUGGAGCCGCCAUCCUCUCUCUGUCCAUCGCAUCCGUCAUUUCGGGCAUUAAUGAGAAGCUUUUCUUCAGUUUGAAAAACACCACCAGGCCAUACCACAGCCUGCCCAGUGAGGCGGUCUUUGCCAACAGCACCGGGAUGCUGGUGGUGGCCUUUGGGCUGCUGGUGCUCUACAUCCUUCUGGCUUCAUCUUGGAAGCGCCCAGAGCCGGGGAUCCUGACCGACAGACAGCUGCUGCUACAGCUGAGGCCUGGAUCCCGGCCUUUCCCUGUGACUUACGUGUCUGUCACCGGCAGGCAGCCCUACAAAUCCUGGUGACCUGCUCUCCCAAGAACAGAGCCUGUCCCCAGAUGUCCCAGUAGCGAUGAGUAACAGAGGUGGCUGUGGACUUCCUCUACUUCUCCUUGCUGGAUCAGGGCCUUCCUGCCUCCCGCUGGGCAGGUCUGGCCUUGCUCUCUUGGCAGGGCCCCAGCCCCUCUGACCACUCUGCAGCUCACCAUGCAGCUGAUGCCAAAGUUGUGGUGUCCAGUGUGCAGCAGCCCUGGGAGCCACUGCCACCUUCAGAGGGGUUCCUUGCUGAGACCCACAUUGCUUCACCUGGCCCCACCAUGGCUGCUUGCCUGGCCCAACCUAGCGUUCUGUGCCAUGCUAGAGCUUGAGCUGUUGCUCUUCUUCAGGGGAGGAAAUAGGGUGGAGAGCGGGAAGGGUCUUGCUCCUAAGUGUUGCUGCUGUGGCUUUUUUGCCUUCUCCAAAGACGCACUGCCAGGUCCCAAGCUUCAGACUGCUGUGCUUAGUAAGCAAGUGAGAAGCCUGGGGUUUGGAGCCCACCUACUCUCUGGCAGCAUCAGCAUCCUACUCCUGGCAACAUCAGGCCAACGUCCACCCCAGCCUCACAUUGCCAGAUGUUGGCAGAAGGGCUAAUAUUGACCGUCUUGACUGGCUGGAGCCUUCAAAGCCACUGGGAUGUCCUCCAGGCACCUGGGUCCCAUGACCAGCUCCCCAUCUCCAUAGGGGUAGGCAUUUCACUGGUUUAUGAAGCUCGAGUUUCAUUAAAUAUGUUAAGAAUCAAAGCUGUCUUUGUUCAGGCUGCUAUAACAAAAAUAUAAUAGCCUGGGUGGCUUAAACAACAA